AUGGCAAAUCUGAGCCAGCCCUCCGAAUUUGUCCUCUUGGGCUUCUCCUCCUUUGGUGAGCUGCAGGCCCUUCUGUAUGGCCCCUUCCUCAUGCUUUAUCUUCUCGCCUUCAUGGGAAACACCAUCAUCAUAGUUAUGGUCAUAGCUGACACCCACCUACAUACACCCAUGUACUUCUUCCUGGGCAAUUUUUCCCUGCUGGAGAUCUUGGUAACCAUGACUGCAGUGCCCAGGAUGCUCUCAGACCUGUUGGUCCCCCACAAAGUCAUUACCUUCACUGGCUGCAUGGUCCAGUUCUACUUCCACUUUUCCCUGGGGUCCACCUCCUUCCUCAUCCUGACAGACAUGGCCCUUGAUCGCUUUGUGGCCAUCUGCCACCCACUGCGCUAUGGCACUCUGAUGAGCCGGGCUAUGUGUGUCCAGCUGGCUGGGGCUGCCUGGGCAGCUCCUUUCCUAGCCAUGGUACCCACUGUCCUCUCCCGAGCUCAUCUUGAUUACUGCCAUGGCGACGUCAUCAACCACUUCUUCUGUGACAAUGAACCUCUCCUGCAGUUGUCAUGCUCUGACACUCGCCUGUUGGAAUUCUGGGACUUUCUGAUGGCCUUGACCUUUGUCCUCAGCUCCUUCCUGGUGACCCUCAUCUCCUAUGGCUACAUAGUGACCACUGUGCUGCGGAUCCCCUCUGCCAGCAGCUGCCAGAAGGCUUUCUCCACUUGCGGGUCUCACCUCACACUGGUCUUCAUCGGCUACAGUAGUACCAUCUUUCUGUAUGUCAGGCCUGGCAAAGCUCACUCUGUGCAAGUCAGGAAGGUCGUGGCCUUGGUGACUUCAGUUCUCACCCCCUUUCUCAAUCCCUUUAUCCUUACCUUCUGCAAUCAGACAGUUAAAACAGUGCUACAGGGGCAGAUGCAGAGGCUGAAAGGCCUUUGCAAGGCACAAUGA